GCGGGCGCCAUCCCGGAAGCGCGAGCAAGGCCGCCAGAUGUGCAGGUGCCGCCGCUACCGACGCCGGGGCCGAGUUUGGGGUGGGGCUGGGGACUCCAGGGCCGCGGGGAACCGGUCCGGGUCGGGCGCGGCCCCCGGGCUGCGGUGGGGUGGGGUGCGCCACUGGCCACAUCUGGUCAUUCCUGCUGCGCACAGGCCUCAGUUUCCCCGUCUGCUCAAUGGAUACGCAGGCGGCGCUACGGGCUGGAUCUGGAUCCGGAUCAGGGGCAUAGGAAUUGGGGCCUCCUGUGUUCUGGGUGUGUCGUGUAACCUGGAGCUGGGCGUUGCCCGGUUUGUGCCUCAGUUUCCCUGUAUUGUAGGGGACGGGGCGUGAGGGGAUAUUUGAGCCCCUCCCCACUUGGGGUUUUUCAGAGCUUGGAUGGCUGAGUUAAAUUCUGUUAAAUAACCUGGAUAUAGAACCGUGGUGCUUCUCUGCCUCUCCCUGUGAGUUUCGGCAACGGAGCCCGCCCCUGUGAGCCUCAGUUUCACUCGGAGAUGAUUGUGUCUGCCUCGUAACGGUGAUUGAGGAUGAAAUGAAGUGCUCUACAAGUGUUUGCCCGUAAUAUAUUCUUAGAGGCCCCUGGGAUGCUCUCAAAAUGUUGAUUCCCGGGACUUCUUCACACUCCUCUUGGAGAAACAGCCUGUCCUGAGCUCCAGUCGUUAUCACCUUUGGUUUCAGUUGCCACAGACAGCACUGUGAGAUCUUCAUUCUACCUUAUUUUCAUUUUAUGGUUGAAAAAACUGAUUCAGAAGGGUGAAGUGGCUCUCCCAUGGUCAAACAGCCUACCUCUCUGCGUUUCUUCAAUAAAUCUACAUUUGGAGUUGGGAUCAGAGCUCUUGCUGGGUCAAUUUCACUGUGUAUGUGGGCCAGACUAGCAGUAAUCAGGGAAGGCUUCUUGGGAGAGGAAGUUGCGGGGGGACGGGAGGGAGGUGCCAGGAACCCCUCAGCCCUCACAUCUGGGAGCCAGAGACAGAAAAGAGUCCUGUUUUGAAGGAGGAGUGUAUCCCAGAAGGUCCCAGUACUGUGUCUCACUGGUACUAGCUAUGGGCCUCCCUCUCCAGGUGUCUUUUUUUUUUUUUUUUUUUUUUUUUCAGUUGAGAUGAAGUCUCCCUCUGUAGCCCACACUAGAAUGCAGUGGCUUGAUUUUGGCUCAUUGCAACCUCUGCCUCCCGGGUUCAAGCGAUUCUCCUGCCUCAGCCUCCUGAGUAGCUGGGACUACAGGUGCCCGCCAUCAUGCCUGGCUAAUUUUUGUAUUUUUAGUAGAGACGGGGGUUUCACCAUGUUCACCAGGCUAGUCUUGAACUCAUGACCUCAGGUGAUCCACCAGCCUUGGCUUCCCAAAGUGCUGAGAUUACAGGCAUGAGCACCCGGUCCAGGUAUCCUCUUUAUACAAGAUCAUGCUUCUUUGGGAAUGUGGAGACUGGGUGUCUCUGCAUGGCAUGUCAUAGGAGUUCAAUAACCAUAGUUAUUAUUAGAGGGAAGGGGGUUUUGCUGGGUGUGGCACCUUAUUUCUAGAAGGUGCUGCAAACCACUGACCAGAUACAGAUCACAAAUAGAUGCUCUUGGCCUCCAUGAUAUCUUGGAAAAAAGUAUUGAUUGCUGACAUUUGUCAAUGAGGCAAUUUCCCAGAAAAAAAAAAUCCCUGUUUCCUUUUUCCUGGAGAAACAUCAGAAGUCAGGCAGAAAUCAGCUGCUGUAAGAAGCCACUGUCCUGUCACAGCUGGAUAUUGUGCACCUGUUCAGAUUCACACCUUUGUGAGACCCGUGGGCUGUGGCCGUUUGUUGUGACUUAGGUUCACUGGCUGUGUGACAGUGGCCCAGUUUCUCAGUGUCCCUGAGCCUCAGUUUUCUCAUCUAUAAAUAAGAAUGAUAACAGUAUGUAUGAGCUUGAUGCUUUGUUUAGCAUAGAGUAGCUGCUGAAUAAAUGGGAGAGUACAUUAAGUGAGCUCUGAAACCCUUUCUUUCUCUUUCCUUUCUUUCUCUCUUUCUCUGUCUCUCUCUCUUUCUCUCCUCUCUCUUUCUCUCUUUGUCUCUCUCUCUUUCUCUCCUUCUCUCUCUCUUUCUCUCUCUCCCUUCCUUCCUUCCCUCCCUCCCUCCCUUCCUUCCUUCUUUUCGAGAUGGAGUCUCACUCUGUCGCCCGGGCUGGAGUGUAGUGGCAUGAUCUCGGCUCAUUGCAACCUCUGCCUCCCAGGUUCAAGCCAUUCUCCUGCCUCAGCCAUCCAAGUAGCUGCGACUACAGGUGCCCGCCACCAUGCCCGGCUAAUUUUUUUUGUAUUUUUAGUAGAGACUGAGUUUCACUAUGUUGGCCAGGCUGGUUUUGAACUCCUGACCUCAAGCAGUCUGCCCACCUCGGCCUCCCAAAGUGCUAGGAUUACAGACGUGAGCCACCACACCCGGCCUCUGAAACCCUUUCUGAUCCAGUAGAAGUUCGUCUCUGUUUCUUGGCUAUUAAAUGUGUGGGCCUCAGAGCCAAACUAUAUCAAGAUCCUAGAUUUUUCCUGAACUCCCUAGGAGGGUCAGUGCUGUAGCCCCUCCUACCCUGGCUGCUCCGGGAAGUCCCUGCCUGCCAUUACGGUCAUCUGUGUGCCAGCAAAACUGGGAACCUCAGAACCAUCUGGAUUGCUGGGGCCCACAGGUUGGCUGCAGCGGAGGAGGAGAAAGAGAUGGACCUCCCGGACUCGGCCUCGAGGGUCUUCUGCGGCCGCAUCCUGAGCAUGGUGAACACAGAUGAUGUCAACGCCAUCAUCCUGGCCCAGAAGAACAUGCUGGACCGCUUUGAGAAGACCAAUGAGAUGCUGCUCAACUUCAACAACCUGUCCAGUGCCCGCCUGCAGCAGAUGAGCGAACGCUUCCUGCACCACACGAGGACCCUAGUAGAGAUGAAACGGGACCUGGACAGCAUCUUCCGCCGUAUCAGGACGCUGAAAGGGAAACUGGCCAGGCAGCACCCAGAGGCCUUCAGCCAUAUCCCAGAGGCAUCCUUCCUGGAGGAAGAGGAUGAAGACCCCAUCCCACCCAGCACCACGACCACCAUUGCCACCUCAGAACAGAGCACGGGCUCAUGUGACACCAGCCCCGACACCGUCUCGCCCUCCCUGAGCCCCGGCUUCGAGGACCUGUCCCAUGUCCAGCCUGGCUCCCCAGCCAUCAACGGCCGCAGCCAGACAGAUGACGAGGAGAUGACGGGCGAAUAGCCCUGCUGCCCGGUGCCUUGAGGGGGUCUCAGGGCAGCAGCAUACAAGAACAUCUCUAUUCUGCAAGACCCCUCUGCCAUGCCAGGGCACGCCCAUUCCAGCUGGAGUCGUGGGGCUGGGCACAGGGGAAUUUUUCCAGAGCUGAGCCUGACGUCUGCUCUGAAGAAUGCUUAGAAGGUUCCCAGACACCAGAGCCAGAUGUCCCCCACCACCGGUCAGGACCUCCUUGAGGUGCACAAGCACGGUCUCCUCUGAGUUCACCCCAGCCCACCCCCGCACCCACUAAUUCUGCUUUUCCUGCCCCUUGCUCCGUAAAAGUAUCAAAUACUUUCUCCUUGGUAUCUCAAGGAGGUUUCUGAGAUAGGUAGAAGUCUUGAGACGGAGGCUGGCCAUCCAUUCAGCCCUGAGCGUGCUGAGUUCUGUGUUUCUCUGAAUAGAGGUGUGGAACCUGAGGGGCCAGCAGGCCUCUCUGAAGGCCUCCAUGGAGCAAACGGAGCCACCUCGGGAAAGAGUUUAAUGGAAUAUUUUUGUACCCGAUGUUUACAGAUGCUGUUGGGAAGUUAUCAAUAAAAAGACACCAUUACUAAAAAGGGAAAA